AGAAACCUGUGUAGCCAGAGAUGGGGACGGAGGCCACAGAGCAGGUUUCCUGGGGCCAUUACUCUGGGGAUGAAGAGGACGCAUACUCGGCUGAGCCACUGCCGGAGCUUUGCUACAAGGCCGAUGUCCAGGCCUUCAGCCGGGCCUUCCAACCCAGUGUCUCCCUGACCGUGGCUGCGCUGGGUCUGGCCGGCAAUGGCCUGGUCCUGGCCACCCACCUGGCAGCCCGACGCGCAGCGCGCUCGCCCACCUCUGCCCACCUGCUCCAGCUGGCCCUGGCCGACCUCUUGCUGGCCCUGACUCUGCCCUUCGCGGCAGCAGGGGCUCUUCAGGGCUGGAGUCUGGGAAGUGCCACCUGCCGCACCAUCUCUGGCCUCUACUCGGCCUCCUUCCACGCCGGCUUCCUCUUCCUGGCCUGUAUCAGCGCCGACCGCUACGUGGCCAUCGCGCGAGCGCUCCCAGCCGGGCCGCGGCCCUCCACUCCCGGCCGCGCACACUUGGUCUCCGUCAUCGUGUGGCUGCUGUCACUGCUCCUGGCGCUGCCUGCGCUGCUCUUCAGCCAGGAUGGGCAGCGGGAAGGCCAACGACGCUGUCGCCUCAUCUUCCCCGAGGGCCUCACGCAGACGGUGAAGGGGGCGAGCGCCGUGGCGCAGGUGGCCCUGGGCUUCGCGCUGCCGCUGGGCGUCAUGGUAGCCUGCUACGCGCUUCUGGGCCGCACGCUGCUGGCCGCCAGGGGGCCCGAGCGCCGGCGUGCGCUGCGCGUCGUGGUGGCUCUGGUGGCGGCCUUCGUGGUGCUGCAGCUGCCCUACAGCCUCGCCCUGCUGCUGGAUACUGCCGAUCUACUGGCUGCGCGCGAGCGGAGCUGCCCUGCCAGCAAACGCAAGGAUGUCGCACUGCUGGUGACCAGCGGCUUGGCCCUCGCCCGCUGUGGCCUCAAUCCCGUUCUCUACGCCUUCCUGGGCCUGCGCUUCCGCCAGGACCUGCGGAGGCUGCUACGGGGUGGGAGCUGCCCCUCAGGGCCUCAACCCCGCCGCGGCUGCCCCCGCCGGCCCCGCCUUUCUUCCUGCUCAGCUCCCACGGAGACCCACAGUCUCUCCUGGGACAACUAGGGCUGCGAAUCUAGAGGAGGGGGCAGGCUGAGGGUCGUGGGAAAGGGGAGUAGGUGGGGGAACACUGAGAAAGAGGCAGGGACCUAAAGGGACUACCUCUGUGCCUUGCCACAUUAAAUUGAUAACAUGGAAAUGAGAUGCAACCCAACAACUGUUACUAUUUUUGAGUCACCGACUUGGAAGUGAUUUGUGGCGGGGCAGAACCGGUGGGUUAACACCCCGCCCCCGCCCCACCCCCCGCCCUGCCCCGCGCUUGGCUCUCUGAGUGGAAGACGCUGAGGGCCUGGGUGGGGGUGGGGGGCUGCUGAGUCUGCUAAAGCUCUAGCCACUGACACCCCCUCCACCGUCACCUGGCCUCAGCCAACAGAGGUGAGGUGGGAAAGCUGCCAGGCAAGGAGGGGCGGUGGUUCCUCUUGCAAUACUGUAAGGAAGAGCUUUCUAACAACCAGAGCGCUCUCCAGUAAUGGCUGCCUUAGCAAAUACUGAGUUCCCGCUAUUGGAAUGUUCAGACUGUCGGGGACGCUGUGGGCCUUUGCGUGGUGUGGGGGGAGGGGGAGGGGCAGGGGAUUCCCGUUUUUGGUGGGCGUUUGGAUUUCAUAACCACUUUACAAUCCCUUCCUAGUGUCUGUGAUGGAAAGAAAAAAUGAAAAAAUGAAUUGUAAAA